AGAGCUGACACUCGGCGAUGAGCUAAGACGCUGUUUCAGAGCGUUUGGGUCCUCUGAGGCCCCUUGACCAGGUGAGCGGACCCUGGAGCUGGGCCCCGGGCUGGGGCGGAACUGCGGCCUAGGGGCCUAGGGAGCAGCUGCUUCCCGGCGGGUGCAGAGAAUCUUCCCUCGACCGAGGGGGCGGGGUCCGUAGCGGAGGUGUCGGCCCUGGGGCCUAUGAGAGUGAUGAAGCUGUGGAUCUGGUAAACAGAGUACAACCUUCUGCUGCAUAUUUUUCAUCCAUUCAGCGCAAUUUUAAGUAGAUAUUAAAGGAGUGUCUCUGAAGAUACAGUCCAAAGAAAGUUCUCCAAAACAAGGAGAACAGUCUGAAGCUGGGGAUGGCAACAGCAUUGGUGAGUGCCCAUUCCCUGGCUCCCCUGAAUCUGAAGAAGGAGGGGCUUCGGGUAGUGAGGGAGGAUCACUACUCUACUUGGGAACAGGGAUUCAAGCUGCAAGGAAACAGUAAAGGCCUUGGACAGGAGCCAUUGUGCAAACAAUUCAGGCAGUUGCGUUAUGAAGAGACCACAGGACCUCGAGAAGCACUAAGUCGGCUCCGGGAGCUCUGUCAACAGUGGCUACAGCCCGAGACCCAUACCAAGGAGCAGAUCCUGGAGCUGCUGGUGCUGGAGCAGUUUCUGAUCAUCCUGCCUAAGGAGCUCCAGGCCCGGGUGCAGGAGCAUCACCCAGAGAGCAGGGAGGACGUGGUUGUUGUUCUGGAGGAUUUGCAGCUGGAUCUUGGAGAAACAGGACAACAGGUGGUAAGGGUCAGAUGUGCUCUUUUUCAGGAAUGCAGGAAUUGAGAUCUCUGGCCAGACAGGUGGACAUGGGCUCAUCAGCGGAAGGAGAAUUACUAAGCUUUGAUUCAGUUUUUUUCCAGUCUAGCUGUUAAUUUCCUUAGGUCUUACCUCAACCUUACCUGGCCCUUGCUUGGAGAAAACUGAAUGUGCACCAGAUUCCCCAUCUUCUUUUCUUUGCCCCUCUGGGGUUUCUCUUUCUUCUCUUUUUUAACACCUAGGUGUUUUACUGAACAGCAGUUUCCUAAACCCACAUAUAUCUAAUUAUGCCUCCAUAUACCUAAUUGUCCCUAGGACCCAGACCAGCCAAAGAAACAAAAAAUACUUGUGGAGGAGAUGGCCCCUCUGAAAGGAGUACAGGAACAGCAGGUUCGGCAUGAGUGUGAAGUUACAAAGCCUGAGAAAGAGAAGGUUGCAGAUUCCUUUCCCCAAGCAUCAAAAGACAAGUAAUUGGUGGUAUAUAUUUAAUAUUGCAGGUGAGGAGACAAGGAUUGAGAAUGGGAAGCUUAUUGUAGUAACAGACUCUUGUGGAAGAGUAGAGUCAUCUGGGAAAAUAUCUGAACCCAUGGAGGCUCAUAAUGAGGGCUCUAACUUGGAAAGGCAUCAGGCCAAGCCCAAAGAGAAGAUUGAGUAUAAAUGCUCAGAACGUGAGCAGAGAUUCAUCCAGCACUUGGACCUGAUUGAACAUGCGAGUACACACACGGGAAAGAAACUCUGCGAGUCUGAUGUGUGUCAGAGUUCCAGUCUUACAGGACAUAAGAAAGUCCUCUCUAGAGAGAAAGGUCAUCAGUGUCAUGAGUGUGGGAAAGCCUUUCAGAGGAGUUCACACCUCGUCAGACAUCAGAAAAUCCAUCUUGGUGAGAAGCCUUAUCAGUGCAAUGAGUGUGGCAAAGUCUUUAGCCAGAAUGCAGGCCUUUUGGAACAUCUCAGAAUUCAUACUGGAGAGAAACCUUAUCUAUGUAUCCAUUGUGGAAAAAAUUUUAGGCGCAGCUCUCACCUUAAUCGACAUCAGAGAAUUCACAGUCAGGAGGAGCCCUGUGAGUGCAAGGAGUGUGGAAAAACCUUUAGUCAGGCCUUACUCCUCACCCACCAUCAGAGAAUCCAUAGUCACUCCAAAAGCCAUCAAUGUAACGAGUGUGGAAAAGCUUUCAGUUUGACCUCAGACCUUAUUCGACACCACAGAAUUCAUACUGGAGAAAAACCUUUCAAGUGUAACAUAUGCCAGAAAGCCUUCCGACUAAACUCACACCUUGCUCAGCAUGUAAGAAUCCACAAUGAAGAAAAACCCUAUCAGUGUAGUGAAUGUGGAGAAGCCUUCAGGCAAAGGUCAGGUCUUUUUCAACAUCAGAGAUAUCACCACAAAGACAAACUGGCUUGAUGAGGUGUUCUCUCCUUGUAGAACAUCAGAGAAGGCACAUUGACUAGCAAACAGCACUUUAGGAAAAGUCACCGUAGCCCACUGUGGCAUCAGAAAAUUCUUGGGGGCUGAGUUGGAGGCUCCCUGCCUCUAUUCUCUCUCCUUUGCUUUCCUUGAAGUCAGCUUUGGACCACAAUAAUUUCACUGUAGAUGAUAUGCUAGGAUCAAAGUUAAACAGCAUUCUUCACUGCAGGACAUCUCAGAGCAUGUAACAUAACUGCAUGAUUAUAUACUCUAAGCAAUAGAGAGCUUCAUGACUGAGUAAGAGUUUUGAAGUCAGCAGUGAAUCAAGUGCCCACAGAUUUGCAGGCUUAAGCAGAACAAGGGAAGAUUGAUAUUUUUGGAUAUGCUAUAGCAGCUUUCUCCUAUGAAAUAAAACUGAUGAUGUUUGGAAGUAUACUACUCUCAAAGGUGUCUUUAAAGUACAGGUUAAUGGUGAACAUUUUCCCCCAGUGGCUUCACCUCAUUCCUCCCACUGGCCUUACCCCUUCCUUCCCCAGUGGAAGCAUUUUCAAAAGCAAAGAUAAUUUUCGCUGGUGAACUUCAGAACUUGCCUUCAGGGUUAGCUUCAUGUAAUUUUACCAUUUCCCAUCCCCAUUCCCCACCACAUUAUGUCAAGAUUCAAGUUAUAAAUUAACGUUUUACUUAGACUUUGAAAGAGAUUUCAUGAGUAAUUUGAAUGAACCUUGCUGAAUUAAUCUGAAUAGCAACUGUCUGACUUGAUAACUCCAGUGCCAGUAUAGUGGCUGCUGCAUAGACACUAUUCAGUAAAUGUCUGAUGAAAGAAAUUGGACUUUUUCCCUUUAAUACUGAUGAUGCAAUUUUGAAAUGUUGCUUGUUCUGGAAUACUUCGGAAGUUAAACAAUAAAGUCAGCUUGGAGAGGAGAUCAUGAUCUUUAUACUGUGAAUAGCAGAAUGUCACAGAUGAAGAAUAUUAAAAUUAGGGGCGUCCACUCCAAAACAUAUCACCAGAGUGACAACUUCAGCCCUCAGCCUCUGCAAUCCAUAUAUAUCCUGGUCUUGGGAGUCCAUAGAAUACUGUUUCCUUCUAAUAAAGGUUUCAAACAAA